AGGCUUCUGGGAUAUGACAGCAUUGCCUUGUGUUAGCUAGCAAUAAGAAAAGAAGCUUUGUUUGGAUUAACAUAUAUACCCUCUUCAUUCUGCAUACCUAUUUUUUCCCCAAUAAUUUGCAGCUUAGGUCCGAGGACACCACAAACUCUGCUUAAAGUCAGUGAACGUUCUCUUUAGCAGGUUUCCAGCAUGUCAGGAAAUGAAAAAGAGCUUCCAGAAGAAUGAUCCAAACUUCUUUCCCAGUCCCAGAAAAGUAGGAACAGCUGAAAUGUACUUGAGGCUAUUGCUCACACAAAAGGAGCAGGUGUUUUGAGAAGGGGCCUGGAGGCUCUCAAGGCAUGGCCAGACGCUCUGUCUUGUACUUCAUCCUGCUGAAUGCUCUGAUCAACAAGGGCCAAGCCUGCUUCUGUGAUCACUAUGCAUGGACUCAGUGGACCAGCUGCUCAAAAACUUGCAAUUCUGGAACCCAGAGCAGACACAGACAAAUAGUAGUAGAUAAGUACUACCAGGAAAACUUUUGUGAACAGAUUUGCAGCAAGCAGGAGACUAGAGAAUGUAACUGGCAAAGAUGCCCCAUCAACUGCCUCCUGGGAGAUUUUGGACCAUGGUCAGACUGUGACCCUUGUAUUGAAAAACAGUCUAAAGUUAGAUCUGUCUUGCGUCCCAGUCAGUUUGGGGGACAGCCAUGCACUGCGCCUCUGGUAGCCUUUCAACCAUGCAUUCCAUCUAAGCUCUGCAAAAUUGAAGAGGCUGACUGCAAGAAUAAAUUUCGCUGUGACAGUGGCCGCUGCAUUGCCAGAAAGUUAGAAUGCAAUGGAGAAAAUGACUGUGGAGACAAUUCAGAUGAAAGGGACUGUGGGAGGACAAAGGCAGUAUGCACACGGAAGUAUAAUCCCAUCCCUAGUGUACAGUUGAUGGGCAAUGGGUUUCAUUUUCUGGCAGGAGAGCCCAGAGGAGAAGUCCUUGAUAACUCUUUCACUGGAGGAAUAUGUAAAACUGUCAAAAGCAGUAGGACAAGUAAUCCAUACCGUGUUCCGGCCAAUCUGGAAAAUGUCGGCUUUGAGGUACAAACUGCAGAAGAUGACUUGAAAACAGAUUUCUACAAGGAUUUAACUUCUCUUGGACACAAUGAAAAUCAACAAGGCUCAUUCUCAAGUCAGGGGGGGAGCUCUUUCAGUGUACCAAUUUUUUAUUCCUCAAAGAGAAGUGAAAAUAUCAACCAUAAUUCUGCCUUCAAACAAGCCAUUCAAGCCUCUCACAAAAAGGAUUCUAGUUUUAUUAGGAUCCAUAAAGUGAUGAAAGUCUUAAACUUCACAACGAAAGCUAAAGAUCUGCACCUUUCUGAUGUCUUUUUGAAAGCACUUAACCAUCUGCCUCUAGAAUACAACUCUGCUUUGUACAGCCGAAUAUUCGAUGACUUUGGGACUCAUUACUUCACCUCUGGCUCCCUGGGAGGCGUGUAUGACCUUCUCUAUCAGUUUAGCAGUGAGGAACUAAAGAACUCAGGUUUAACCGAGGAAGAAGCCAAACACUGUGUCAGGAUUGAAACAAAGAAACGCGUUUUAUUUGCUAAGAAAACAAAAGUGGAACAUAGGUGCACCACCAACAAGCUGUCAGAGAAACAUGAAGGUUCAUUUAUACAGGGAGCAGAGAAAUCCAUAUCCCUGAUUCGAGGUGGAAGGAGUGAAUAUGGAGCAGCUUUGGCAUGGGAGAAAGGGAGCUCUGGUCUGGAGGAGAAGACAUUUUCUGAGUGGUUAGAAUCAGUGAAGGAAAAUCCUGCUGUGAUUGACUUUGAGCUUGCCCCCAUCGUGGACUUGGUAAGAAACAUCCCCUGUGCAGUGACAAAACGGAACAACCUCAGGAAAGCUUUGCAAGAGUAUGCAGCCAAGUUCGAUCCUUGCCAGUGUGCUCCAUGCCCUAAUAAUGGCCGACCCACCCUCUCAGGGACUGAAUGUCUGUGUGUGUGUCAGAGUGGCACCUAUGGUGAGAACUGUGAGAAACAGUCUCCAGAUUAUAAAUCCAGCUUAUGGGAACAAAGUCUAAAAGGAAAUCAGGCAAUGUGUCAGGCCCCUUGCACAGAUGCAGUAGACGGACAGUGGGGUUGUUGGUCUUCCUGGAGUACCUGUGAUGCUACUUAUAAGAGAUCGAGAACCCGAGAAUGCAAUAAUCCUGCCCCCCAACGAGGAGGGAAACGCUGUGAGGGGGAGAAGCGACAAGAGGAAGACUGCACAUUUUCAAUCAUGGAAAACAAUGGACAACCAUGUAUCAAUGAUGACGAAGAAAUGAAAGAGGUCGAUCUUCCUGAGAUAGAAGCAGAUUCCGGGUGUCCUCAGCCAGUUCCUCCAGAAAAUGGAUUUAUCCGGAAUGAAAAGCAACUAUACUUGGUUGGAGAAGAUGUUGAAAUUUCAUGCCUUACUGGCUUUGAAACUGUUGGAUACCAGUACUUCAGAUGCUUACCAGACGGGACCUGGAGACAAGGGGAUGUGGAAUGCCAACGGACGGAGUGCAUCAAGCCAGUUGUGCAGGAAGUCCUGACAAUUACACCAUUUCAGAGAUUGUAUAGAAUUGGUGAAUCCAUUGAGCUAACUUGCCCCAAAGGCUUUGUUGUUGCUGGGCCAUCAAGGUACACAUGCCAGGGGAAUUCCUGGACACCACCCAUUUCAAACUCUCUCACCUGUGAAAAAGAUACUCUAACAAAAUUAAAAGGCCAUUGUCAGCUGGGACAGAAACAAUCAGGAUCUGAAUGCAUUUGUAUGUCUCCAGAAGAAGACUGUAGAAAUGCUUGCUUUCCUCUCUUGGGCAGCCAUCAUUCAGAAGAUCUCUGUGUGUUUGACACAGACUCCAACGAUUACUUUACUUCACCCGCUUGUAAGUUUUUGGCUGAGAAAUGUUUAAAUAAUCAGCAACUCCAUUUUCUACAUAUUGGUUCCUGCCAAGACGGCCGCCAGUUAGAAUGGGGUCUUGAAAGGACAAGACUUUCAUCCAACAGCACAAAGAAAGAAUCCUGUGGCUAUGACACCUGCUAUGACUGGGAAAAAUGUUCAGCCUCCACUUCCAAAUGUGUCUGCCUAUUGCCCCCACAGUGCUUCAAGGGUGGAAACCAACUCUACUGUGUCAAAAUGGGAUCAUCAACAAGUGAGAAAACAUUGAACAUCUGUGAAGUGGGAACUAUAAGAUGUGCAAACAGGAAGAUGGAAAUACUGCAUCCUGGAAAGUGUUUGGCCUAGCACAAUUACUGCUAGGCCCAGCACAAUGAACAGAUUUACCAUCCCGAAGAACCAACUCCUACAAAUGAGAAUUCUUGCACAAACAGCAGACUGGCAUGCUCAAAGUUACUGACAAAAAUUAUUUUCUGUUAGUUUGAGAUCAUUAUUCUCCCCUGACUCUCCUGUUUGGGCAUGUCUUAUUCAGUUCCAGCUCAUGACGCCCUGUAGCAUACCCCUAGGUACCAACUUCCACAGCAGUCUCGUAAAUUCUCCUGUUCACAUUGUACAAAAAUAAUGUGACUUCUGAGGCCCUUAUGUAGCCUGUGACAUUAAGCAUUCUCGCAAUUAGAAAUAAGAAUAAAACCCAUAAUUUUCUUCAAUGAGUUAAUAAACAGAAAUCUCCAGAACCUCUGAAACACAUUCUUGAAGCCCAGCUUUCAUAUCUUCAUUCAACAAAUAAUUUCUGAGUGUGUAUACAGGAUGUCAAGUACUGACCAAAGUCCUGAGAACUCGGCAGAUAAUAAAACAGACAAAAGCCUUUGCCUUCAUGAAGCAUACAUUCAUUCAGGGGUAGACACACAAAAAAUGAAAUAAACAGGUAAAAUAUGUAGCAUGUUUGAUGGUGAUAAUUGUUUUGGAGAAAAUACAACACGGAAGGGUGAGUCCCAUCCUUAAUUAUCAUCUUAUGCAAGGAAAUAUUCCAUAACAAUAAACAUCGCUGUAAGGAUGA